GGGACGCUGAGGGGCCCGAGGAGACCGUGAGGCUCUGGCCUGCAGCUCGCGCCGCCAUGGACGCUGCCGAGGUCGAAUUCCUCGCCGAGAAGGAGCUGGUUACCAUUAUCCCCAACUUCAGUCUGGACAAGAUCUACCUCAUCGGGGGGGACCUGGGGCCUUUUAACCCUGGUUUACCCGUGGAAGUGCCCCUGUGGCUGGCGAUUAACCUGAAACAAAGACAGAAAUGUCGCCUGCUCCCUCCAGAGUGGAUGGAUGUAGAAAAGUUGGAGAAGAUGAGGGAUCAUGAACGAAAGGAAGAAACUUUUACCCCAAUGCCCAGCCCUUACUACAUGGAACUUACGAAGCUCCUGUUAAAUCAUGCUUCAGACAACAUCCCGAAGGCAGACGAAAUCCGGACCCUGGUCAAGGAUAUGUGGGACACUCGUAUAGCCAAACUCCGAGUGUCUGCUGACAGCUUUGUGAGACAGCAGGAGGCACAUGCCAAGCUGGAUAACUUGACCUUGAUGGAGAUCAACACCAGCGGGACUUUCCUCACACAAGCGCUCAACCACAUGUACAAACUCCGCACGAACCUCCAGCCUCUGGAGAGUACUCAGUCUCAGGACUUCUAGAGAAAGGCCUGGUGCAGGCGGCUUGCUGGGGGAUGUGAGCGCUCAGGACGUGAUGAGGUACUCGUGGUUCUGGAGCUCUAGAAACACUUCUGAUGCAUGAAAAAUGUGUGAUGGUGCAAGGAAUGGAUUCAGGAUGUUGUUGGAGAAACAAGUUUGUGAUUAGUCCUUAAAACUUAGCUCCCUGGGACAUUCUUCAAUUCCACAUCUGUUUCUAGAAACCAGCCCUUUUUCCCCCCACUUUUGAGAAAUAAAAAAGCCUUAGGUAAAUAAGUCAUUCUCCCUAGCAGAGCCACUUGGGUCUCCUGCAUGGAAGCCAUCACACUUGGGCAGGUGUUCAGUGACUGGUAGGUGUAGAUACAGCAGGAGUGGCCAUGUGGUCCACGGCUUUUUACCCCUUCUUGAUCCUGAUUUCUUGGGCUGAAUUUAGACUCUCUCACAGAGGUGGCUCACAGAGAAGGAUGGCAGAUGGUGCAGCCAACAAUGCUGACCGGUGCUUAUCCUCUAAGCCCUGAUCCACAAUAAAAAUGGACCCAACUCAGCUCUGACUCUCUAGGUUUUUGUGCUGCGUAACUACCAAGUAAAAGGACUGAGCCUGUGGCUGAGAUGACUCAGUCAACGAAACUGAGGCACACGGCAGUUAAGUGGAAACUGCAGACCAACACCUGGGGUGUCUCCUUCUCUUGGCUACUUCUAGCUCAGGUUUAAUGGGUUGCUUAUCAAGAGGAGAGUCAGGAAAAAAACGAAUCCAAUGUAUUGAGCAUGAGUGACAAUGUAUUGAGCAUGAGUGACAAUGCUAGAAGAAAAGUCACUUUCAGUGCUGCUCUUGAUGGAUUUGGGGAAGGAUUCUUUGUUGUAGGUAACAGUGGGCUCAGGGGAAAUUAUUUUUUUCCUAAGAGAAAAUUACUUUAUUCGUAGCAUUUUGGAAAUGUUAGGACCUUUACAGAAAUUACAUUACCUUGAGAGGUGAAAUGAUCGUCCAGCAUCAUGCAAUGGAUAGAAGGUUCUGUAAUCAGCUUUAAAAAAAACUUUAAUUUUUGGCCGGGCACAUUGGCUUGGCUCAUGCAUGUAAUCCCAGCACUUUGGGAGGCCAAGGCAGGUGGAUCACAAGGCCAGGAGAUUGAGACUAUCCUGGCUAACAUGGUGAAACCCCGUCUCUAUUAAAAAUACAAAAAAAAAAAAAUUUGCCAGGUGUGGUGGCACACGCCUAUAGUCGCAGCUACUCGGGAGGCUGAGGCAGGAGAAUCGCUUGAACCCGAGAGGCGGAGGUUGUAGUGAGCCAAGAUUGCACCACUGUACUCCUGCCUGGGCAACGAGAGCAAGACUCUGUCUCAAACAAAAAAAAUUUUAACUUUUUUUUUAGACAGGGUCUCGUUCUGUCAUCCAGGCUGCAGUAGAGUGGCGUGAUUAUAGCUCACUGCAGCCUCGAACUCCUGGGUUCACACAGUUCUCCCACCACAGCCUCCCAAAGCACUGGGAUUGCAAGCAUGAGCCGCCAUGCCUGGCCAGCCUAUUUUUGGCUGGACACCAGUGGGCCAAAAGCAGUGGGGUGCUGUCUGGGGAGCUCUGAGAAUGCGCAUGUGUGACAGGCUGAGCCUAAAGACUUAUCACCCAGCAUCUGCCCUCCAGUGUCUAGCAUGCUGCACACUAUCACUCCAUGUUGCUGCCCACGUGUCCCCGCCAGGCAGGUUUUGGUGGUUAUUUGGACACUGAAGGGUCAGACCUGGAAGACUGGGACCAAAAGAUGAGGUCUCCAUAAUUUAAGGUGCUGUUCAGACUUGGUUCAGCUCAUAGGACUUGUUCUUUCAUCUCAGCCUUCCUUGGAAUCCUCCUGCUUUCAUCUGGGGAUCUUUUAGAAUGAAACCACUUGUUAUUGUGGAGGGCAAGGGGUCCUAAUGCCCUCCUCUUAGAGCCUGAGCCAGUGGAGGCAGCUCCGUCUGCGGAGAUGUAUAGUUAUUGAGCUUUUCUUUGUUUGGCUUUGUUUUAUAUCAUAAAAAAGAUUUUCCUCUUAACAUAA